AUUCCUCGCGAGUGUAUGGCGUGGGCUCCCUUCCCCCUCUGUGGGUCCCGCGAGGAGACUCUCGGGCUUUGAGGUGAGACCUGAAGUUCCGCUGGCCGGUAGUGUAGCAGGAAAGGGCAGGUCCUCCCGGGUCGUGAGCCAGUAGCCUCCUGGGGUGGCAAGGUGUAGAGAGGGGGGCGUUGAAAGGACACCCGCUACCCGGCCUGCUUUCUAGGGGUCUCUUUGGAUUGAGGACAUCAGCAGCAGUGGAAGGGAUUUUACUGGAGACCUGUCACUGUCAGAGCCUUAAAAUAUCACCGACGGGGCCUUAAUGUCACCGAGGUAGAGAGAAAAGGGCAGUAGCCCUAGAGACUAUUGCGACACAGUGUGCCCCUCAUAAGUUUUUCCAGGGAGGGGUUCUGUACUGAGUUGACGCCCCAGGAGCUGAGCACCAGGCUUUGCAUCCUUGGGAACUCAGCAAACGUUUGUUCAGCCAAUUGCAGGUAGCAUGGCCCAGGGCUUGAUUGAGGUGGAGCGAAAGUUCCUUCCAGGGCCUGGCACAGAGGAGCGGCUGCAGGAGUUGGGGGGCACCCUGGAGUACCGGGUCACCUUCCGAGACACCUACUAUGACACCCCUGAGCUGAGCCUCAUGCAGGCUGACCACUGGCUGCGACGACGAGAGGAUAGUGGAUGGGAGCUCAAAUGUCCUGGAGCAGCAGGUGUCUUAGGACCCCACACGGAGUAUAAGGAACUCACAGCGGAACCUACAAUUGUGGCCCAACUCUGUAAGGUGCUGCGGGCUGACGGCCUGGGGGCUGGAGAUGUGGCUGCUGUGCUGGGCCCACUGGGGCUGCAGGAAGUAGCUAGUUUUGUGACUAAGCGGAGUGCCUGGAAGCUGGUGCUCUUGGGAGCUGAUGAAGAGGAGCCACAGCUCAGGGUGGACUUGGAUACAGCCGACUUUGGCUACGCUGUGGGUGAGGUAGAGGCCCUGGUGCAUGAGGAGGCUGAAGUACCAACUGCCCUAGAGAAGAUCCACAGGCUCAGCAGCAUGCUUGGUGUGCCUGCACAGGAGACAGCACCAGCCAAGCUGAUUGUGUAUCUACAGCGUUUCCGGCCUCAAGACUAUCAGCGCCUGCUAGAAGUGAACAGCUCCAGAGAGAGGCCACAGGAGACUGAAGAUCCUGACCACUGCCUGGGCUAGGGGUGUCACUUCCUAGAAGGGGAAGGGAACUCUGGGUCUAACGGAGUCCACUCCUGGGCCCACUGUGCCUCUCCCCUCAGUGUCCCUUCUGACAGUGACUCCUCUCUCUCCAGCGCUGCCUGUUUCUUCCCCCUCCUCUAAGCUACUCUUCCUUGAGCCCUCCCUGGCUGCUUCCUCUCGCUCAUCCGUCAGAUGCAAUCUGUGGGCCGCCCCUCUCCCCUGGCCGCUAAGCAGCCUCCAUUGAUUUCCGCUCGUGUUUAUAGGAUUUCCACUUAGCCGUGAUCAGUAGUUAAGCACAGGAAAAUCCCUUGCCACCCCCCCUCCCUUGGUCGAUGCCAUUGAUUCUGCCAGCGGCUCCUAAACCGCCUUACAGCUGAGUUAGAAGAUGAGGAGAGGCAGCAGGGAUUUCCCUGCCUUGGGAUGUGGGAAACAGAAGAAAAGUUGAGGAAAUGGUUGGGAAUCGCUGUUAGAACUCUAGAAAUUCUAAUCUGACUUUGCCACUGUGCCCAGCUCUGGCCCAGAGGGUAGAGUGCCUCCUGUGGAAGUUUAGGGGCAAAUUUGUUCCCUGACCUGGAGAGGGUUAGAAAGAACCAACAGCUGCCCCCUCCCCGCCCCCGUGUUGAGACAGGUUCUCAAGGCUCAGGGGAAGAUGCAUACCUCCUAUGUAAGAAUGCUCUUCCCUUGCUGUUAUUCAUACACACUUUCCACUUCAAAUAUACCCAAAUAUGGCUUUCCUCACUUCUCAGGCUUUAUUGGGCUUUAUUUGUGGGAGAAGGGGGCUGGUCCCCAGUUUUUGCAGUGCAAAGCCAGAGCGCCACCUGCUGGUAGCCCUCAGGUGUAGGUUCGAAGCUGCUGGGGCCCCCUGGGGUUUGGGACACAGGAGAAUUUCAGGCUGUGAGUGGAGACAGUUACUGCCACGAUUCCACAGGCAAGUUGUUCACCUCAAAGAUCUCCUGCACCGACUGGUGAAAGUGGUCGUAGGUGAGGCGCAGCUUUAGCCGCAGGGGGGCCUAGGAAUAGGAGAGCAGGGACCAGGGUUAGCACCCACGGCUUCUUCUAUCCCUGGGUCUUGUCUUGGGGGAACUCCUGAAGCUCACCUUGUUAGGAUUGAGGAUUCUGAAGAGCUGGGUGAUAGGAAGGCCACCCCGAGCUGGAACUGUGUUCCCACUGGGGGCCUGCAGCUGCAGCUGGAGACUCUGAACACAGGAGUUUAACAGAGCACAGUAUGGCAGUAGGUAGGGCUCAGGCAGCCCCUCUAUACUCAGUGGCUCCACACCCUUUUCCUGUAACUCCCCAAGUGCUGAUCUCCAGAUGACUCAAUCCCAUCUCACACUGUCUCCCACCCACCUCCUCCACUUAGUGGCCUUUUCUCCUGGAGUCCCCAGGCCACCUCUGAACUCUGAUCUUUACAAACCUUGGGCACAGCAGCCU